CUCUGCGUGCGCCGGAGGCUGCCGUGGCGGGUGGGCCGCCUGACUUCUCCUCCCGGCCAGUUCUCGAGCGCCUCACCGGGCCUCGCCCUGCAGCCUCGCUCUCGCUGGCGCUGCGCGGCCUAGGGGACUGGGCUGCUGGCCUCCGGGUGCGGGGUGGGGGCAGGCUCCGACCUGGGGCGUCCUGGCCGCGCGAGCCGCGGGAUGGGGGCCCGGGCCGCGGAGGAGGCGCCGCUGGUGUGUCCCUUGGUGGAGAGGGCGCUGCCGGCCCUGCGCGGUUUCCAGCCAGGAAGCUUCGGGAAGCCUGGACGUCUGCUCACUGGAGAUGACACGUGCGUGGGGUGUUGGCAUUCUUGUUAUUUAACACGGGAAGGAGGUGACUUCGCCUGUGAUGGACUUCCAGUGUGAGCACUGGCCAGAGUGACCAGGCUGACCAGCACCAGCCCUGAUCCAGAUGCAGAGGCCAGGAUGUGGGCCCAGCCCUGUGCCAGGAGGCUGGCUGGAAUAAAGAGUAACAAACCCCCUUGGAGGACUCUCCUGCCGGGAUGUCCAUGUCCGCCUUUGCUCCGAGCUGGGGUCUCAUGUCUGUGGUGCUGGAAUCCAGAGCCCUGACGGUAGGGGAGUGAUUUUGCAACACAGUUGCAUUUCACAUCUUCUGACAGGAUUCCUUGAGGGAGGGUUGGACCCUGGCACCUGGCCAGCUCCAGGAAGGGUGGCCAGGCCCCUCACUGCCCCAUCAAGAGUACUUGGUGUUGGAGAUCUUCUUCCAGAGCAGAGUCUUGAGGUGGCUGAGCACCAGCGAGUGAUGGGCCUCCACCUGGCUGGCCAGCCCGCUCAGCGUGGUACAGGUGCGCAGCUGUGUGCCCAGCUCCUCGCGGAGGUCGGCGGGCGCGCCAGGCAGCAGGUAGCCCCGUAGCAGUGCGCACACCUUGGCCAGGUUGGGCUGGAUGAGGUCGCCCUUGCACUGCCUCAUGAGCCUGUCACACGGGGCCCUGCAGUCGCGCCCGUAGGUGCAGUCGGUGCUGUGCUCGCAGCGGCGGCCCUGCAGGAAGCGGCGCACGGUGGCCUCGGGUGCCACCUGCUGCAGGUCGGCCAUCUUGAAGUCGUAGGUGGCUGUGUAGCCCACGUUGGCCAGUGUGGUCUCACACAUGUAGAAAGUCCCGUAAGAGCCGUGGAAGAGCUCCUCCACGAACUCCAGCAGGCCGAUGGCGAUCUUGGCCCGCCAAGGCCACGCAGGCCCCAGCCACUGCUGGAGAGCACCCUGCAGGGCAGGCGGCAGCAGUGGGCGCAACAGGGGUGGAAGGGCGGCCGCGUGCCAGGCGCCAUGCGGCACGCCCUCGGUGAGGUAGAGGUCCCCACAGUAGCCCAGCAGUCUGGAGGCGUGCUCCUUCUCCUGCAGGGACAGCAGCAGCAGGAACUCGUUACGCUGCAGCAGGGCCCACACGGACUUGGCUUCCGCCAGGGACACCCGGUUGUCCUUGUUGAAGUCAGCCAUGAGCAGGACCUGGCCAACCAGCGCCGGCAGGGAAGGCAGGUCUCCCAGGUUCGCCUGGCGUUUGGGACCAAAAGAAAGGAAAAGCCAGCUGAUUUGAUGUCUGGGAGCACGACCUGGCCUUUACCUGGUCCUCCUGGCGGGGUGGUCUGCCGGCCAGACCAGCACAUCUGCCAGGUUAGGGGUCCCAGCCCACAGCUACACGGGUGGAGGACGCAGCCAGCAAUGUGUCAGCUCACUCUGCUGGCCUGUGUGGCUGCUGCCAGACAGACCUCCCGCCUCCUGGCAGCCUUGGGUGCACCUGGGGAGCUCGGGGGUGGGCACCUGGGCAGAGAAGCCUCAGAGCUUCCCUGAGGAUGAGAAUCGGCACAGGGCAGAGGGCACGCACUGGCUGAAGCCCUGGGAAGCGGCCCCUUUCCACAAGCCCUGGUCUCCAUUCGGGGCACCUGCCCUGCUGGACACACGGCCCUUGACUGCAGGAGCCUCCCCUCGACCUCAGCUGCCAGCCCACCGGCGCCCCCAACCCUUGCCCCCAGCCCUGGAGAGGCUCCUUCCCUGGCAGGGCUCAUGCCCAGGGGCUGGGGGAUGGGAGGUCUGCCCAGGGUCCACUUGGGCCCAUCUGUGCCUUUGCGCUGGGCAUGUUGGUGCCAGGGCCGCCUGCUGGGCAUAUGACCGUGGUGUGGACUCCUGCCCUGCCCCCUAGGAGAGCUGCCUGACCUUGAGGAAGCUGAGGGUCAUCUCCCGGAAUUCCUUGAUGGAGGUGCCCCGGGUGGGCUUGUCAAACAGUACCAGCUCCCGCCGGGGGGCCGCAUCCGACCGGGCCUUGGAGUCGAGGGUCUCCUCAAUGCCACACUUGAUGGUUACAUCCUUGUCCCGCCAGAGCCCGCUGUACACCUGGACAGGGCCACAGAGGUCCUCCGUGCAGACAUCCCCCUCCCACUGCACGGGCAGUAUCAGCCCCAGGCCCACCCGCCCUGCCAGUGGCUAUACCUGCUGGCCCGGGGCCACCGAGAGGCAGGUCCUCCACUCCACCAUAUGCAGCUCACACAGGUCCUGGCAGACGGAGCCCGAGAUGAUCCCCUUGCGGUACUGGUCACACUGAGGAGACAGGUGCAGGCGUGCCGGGCGGGGCAGCCACACCCCUGCCCCACUGAGCCCCUGCCCACAGGCCCGAAGCUGGCAGGGGCCUCCACUUGCUGCAGUUGGAAAGCUGCCAGCCCCUCACACAGGCAGUGCCGGGGCCCUGGGUCAUGCCAUUGGUGGCUGCAGGAUGGGGCUGUCGGCUGCAGGGGCAGCCCCGCCAACCCUCCGGUCCGGUCCCGUCCCCACCAUCCUGGCUCCUGUAACAGGACGGCACAGCAAAGGCCACUGCCUGGACAUGAGACACACACCACACCCAGUGUCGACCCCACGCCAGGGCCAGAGGCAGGAACCUGGAGGCAGCUCUCCGCCCAGCCGACCCAGCUCUGGACCAUCCAGGCAUUGGCCGGUGAACUAGAAUUCACACUAGUCCCUAAUAUCUACACCACCAGCUGCCACACGCGCGCUCUCUGCCUGACUCUUCAUUCCUGCCUCGGGUGACGCCAGGAGGGAGGAUGCACCCCCUGACUCAUGGCGCCCUCCCUGCCCGGAAUAGUAAGUGAGACAUUUCUGAACUUGUUUCCUAUGAUGGUGCUGACUGGACUGCGUCUUCCAUCUGAAGGGCCAGGAGCUGCCCCACCCAGGCAGGGCUUUCCCUGGGACGCCAGGAAGAACAAAAGGGUGGGCUCUUGGUGCCAGAGCGAUGGAUGGUCAGGCUGGCAGAACCUGGACAGGAGUCAGACACGAGCCAUAGGGCCUCUGUCAGAGAAGCAACCCCCUGGACACAGGGCAAACAGCUGGGUGUCAUCCCGUGAAGGGCACCGCGUCCAGCCCCUCUGCUCCCCGUCAGGGCGGGCUGCCAGCCAUUCUGCACUGGGCACUCAUGGGGGCUCUCACGACAGAUCCUGAUGCCCAGAGCCACACCUGCAUGGCAGCUUCUGGCUGGGUUUCCACUAAUCUCAGGUGUGGGUCUCCUCCUGUCCCAAGGACUUGGCCUCCCUCUUUGGCCCGGCCCAGCCUUCCCCAGGCUGAGGCAGGAGGACAGGCUGCGGCCUCACUGUUUGCCUCAAGUGCAGCCAGGACAGGGCUCACCACCAGAGCUGACAGUCUCAAGGGUACCCCUGGGGUGGAGCCGGCAACGGAGCCCCAGCCUCUACCUCCUCUCCCAGCCCUCCGAGGCCAGUGCCCAGGCUCAAGCGCUCCGUUGUCAGAGCUGUUUGUCAAGGCUGAGAAAACGGACCCCUGGGGCCCCACAAUGACUCCGGGCCUGUCCUUCCCUGUCCCACAGGCCCCCUCCUUAGCCAGACCCCCAGGGAGACUUUGUUAGCAGUAAUUACAUCAGGCCUGGGGCUGGCUGCCGCCCCUCCUCAGCCCCCACCCUAGCUCCAGGGGCCUGGCAGCCCCUCAAUCCCAGCGCCCCACGGGAGGUGAUGGAGGGAUGGAGCUGGCCCGCCCCUCUGGGGGGGGGAGAAUUCCUGGAUGUACAGCCUCAGUUGCCAUGGAGCCUGGCCAAGCAGGCUUGGAGGGAGCUGGGGAAGGGAGCUGCGGAACACCCCGCCCUCCAGGGUUGGGGAGGAGGGAGGGUCCCCGCCCCCCACACACCAAGGAUGGGGACAGAAGUGAGAUGGGCCAACUGGAGGCCGAGGACCCCGCCACGUGAGUCAUGAAGGCAGCGUCUGUCCCGGCAGCAAGAAAACGCCGGCUCUUCGUCAAGACAGAAAAGGAAAAUGAAGGAAAACUGCACACUUGUCCAACCCUCCACCUUGCAGGCAGGCCCUUUGCCACCGGAGUCCACUCCCGUCCCCAGACCAGCCAGCUCCCUGCACCCAGAGCCCCAGACCACACAGCCCCUGCACCCGGAACCCCAGACCAGCCCCCUGCACCCGGAGCCCCAGACCAGCCCCUGCGCCUGGAACCCCAGACCACACAGCCCCCUGAACCCAGAGCCCCAGACCAGCCCCUGCACCCGGAGCCCCAGCCCACACAGCCCCCUGCACCCGGAGCCCCAGACCACACAGCCCCCUGCACUCGGAGCCCCAGAUCACACAGCCCCUGCGCCCGGAGCCCCAGACCAGCCCCUGUGCCCGGAGCCCCAGGACCGCAGGAGGCUGCCCUGCUCCUGGCACACAGUGGUGCUGGGGAAGGAGCCUGUGGGCCACACUGCUGUCUGCCAGGCUGGGGCUGGGGCUGGGGCUCCAGGGUCCCCCAGGGGUGGGGAGAUGGAGCUGCCUCCAUGGUCCUGGGCACCUACCAGCACCUAGCAGAGUGUGGAGAGGCUUCCUCAGAGGCUGAGGCGGGCGUGUGCUUGGCCUCCUCAGGGCCCUUGCCGCACAUCGGUCCCCUCACCGCCCAGCCUGUUCCCCGCCUGCAGCAGGGCUCAGUGGGGACUCACGGUCUAGUUCUUGGCCUCGCGAGGGCCCUGGUGGAAGCUGGGACUGGCCCUGCACUGCUGCUGCCUCGUUGUGUGCGCUGGGCCAGCCUCUGCGCCUCUCUGAGGCGUCCAAUGCCCCCACGAGGCCGGGCAGGGAACCUCCUCUGGGAAGGAGGGGACGUCUCCAUGGCCCCUGGGGUGGCUUCGGGAGAGCUGGGCUUGGCCUGACCUCUGGGAAGGCUCUGAGCAGCCAGGGAAACCCCCACUGGGCAAAGGGCCAGGGCACCCUGGGAAACCGACGCUGCAGCUUCCUCUUGUUUGUGGGGGCACCUCCUCCUGCUUUGCGGCCCGGCACCCAGUAGGUGCUCAGAACCUGCCUGGCCACGUGAAUCCUCUGCUCACCCCCACCCGCCCCCACCCACAACAUCCCGGCCCGGAGGUCCGGCCCCUCCACCUCCUUGGUCCUUCUAGGAGCUCCAGGGGUGCAUCUGAUCGGGGCACAGCCUUCCCCACCCAUGGCCCCAGGACGAGCCCCAUGUGCCACCCUCCGGCCCUGCUGGGCUCAGAGGCCCCCUGGACUUCAAGGGUGAGCAAGGCCUGGUCCAGGGGCCCGGAGGCCUCCCCUGGGCUGGCAUGGGCUCCAAACAAGUCCUGGGCACAGAAGCUCUCCUAGCUCCGGACCCCACACCCCAGUCCUCCACUGCCACAUCUGGGCCUUUCCACAUGUGGCCCCCGUCAGACAUGGCUCUGUGGGACACAGGCCUGCCCAGGCCCACCCGGCUAGCUUCAUCCACCACCCAGUUGCCAGGAGAGGUGCUCUCCCCAUCUGACGGAGGAGACACCGAACCUGGGGUCUCCCUGCACCCAAUCACCCUAUGACAACCCACAGUGGCCGCUGCUACAGGCCAGAUCCUUCUAUGCCCAGGCCUGACCCCAAGGGGAGUGGAGGCAUCGGAACCCUGGUCAUCGGGCAGCCUGGGGUCAAAAUUCAGUGGGGGACCUGCCCAGUUCUGGGCGAGUCUAGGGUUUGCCAGGAAGACAGAGCUGGGAUGACCUCCCCUCUGAGCUAGUCACAGGGUGUGGAGAGGGGCAGGGGGUCACCUUGGUGUGCACUCAUGUGGACACGUUUGCUCCCAGACACACACAUGCUCACAUACGCCAGGGGACUUAGCCCUAUCUCCCUGAGGUGGAGGCUGUGGAGGACCUUGCCCUGCCACCUGCCUCAGGGGACCCCUGGUCCCAGGGGGGCUAGCGAGGCCACUAAGGCCAGCACACGGGGGUCUCUAUCCCGGACCAGUGAGGCCAGCACACGGGGGUCUCUAUCCCGGACCAGUGAGGCCAGCACACAGUGGUCUCUAUCCUGGACCAGUGAGGCCAGCACACGGUGGUCUCUAUCCCAGGCCAGUGAGGCCAGCACACGGGGGUCGCUAUCCUGGACCAGUGAGGCCAGCACACGGGGGUCUCUAUCCCAUCCAGUGAGGACACCACACGGGGGUCUCUAUCCCGGAGCAGUGAGGCCAGCUGCCCACCCCAGGCUUCCUGCUAAACAUCCUCCCUCCCAAAGAUUUCUGGAGUCUGCCCUGCCUUCUGCCCCCAGCCCCCACGUCUCCCCCAUCCUCCUCUGGACCCCCAUCCUCCACACCCAGCCUGAGGCAGCCCCGCACGUCUCCCCCGUCCUCCCCUGGACCCCUGUCCUCCACACCCAGCCUGAGGCAGCUUUGCAGAUUCCACCUAGAAACCCACGUGCCUCGUGGGCCCUGGGUCUGGGGAGGAAGGUGUCUCCAGGGCCUGGUGCCCCAGCAUCUUGGGCAGCAGGGGGCACGGCCCAGUCCCCAGCCCGCACAAGCAACACUUACAAUGACCACCUGGCAGACAUGGCCGCGACAGCGCUCCGAGUAGGACGAGUAGUGCACGUACACCAGCCAGCUGCCUGCAAAGACGCCCAGCCAGGCCAGGAAGAUGCAGCGGACCCUGAGGCCUGGGAGCCGGCCCUGUGGGGGAAGGGGCUGCGUGAGGAGGUGCCCUCGGGGCACCCAGGCUCAGGGUGCUCUCAACCCCACUUCCCACAGGAAGGGCCUCCGGAUCCACCCCAGCCUUCCCCUGCCAUCCCCUUGGCCCCCUGGCACCCCCGUCUUCUAGAAUCACCCCCAGCUCAGCGACACCCACUCCUGGCUCUGCCUCUCCAGGGUCACAUACCAGGGGCUGCAGGGGCCGGAGGUGGGGGCAGGCGCUGCCCAGACUUUUCAGUGUUAUGGGCAGGUACAAAUAAAUGUCAAAACCAGGGGA